ACACACACACACAAGCACACACGCGCUCACACACAGAGAGAAAAUCCUUCUGCCUGUUGAUUUAUGGAAACAAUUAUGAUUCUGCUGGAGAACUUUUCAGCUGAGAAAUAGUUUGUAGCUACAGUAGAAAGGCUCAAGUUGCACCAGGCAGACAACAGACAUGGAAUUCUUAUAUAUCCAGCUGUUAGCAACAAAACAAAAGUCAAAUAGCAAACAGCGUCACAGCAACUGAACUUACUACGAACUGUUUUUAUGAGGAUUUAUCAACAGAGUUAUUUAAGGAGGAAUCCUGUGUUGUUAUCAGGAACUAAAAGGAUAAGGCUAACAAUUUGGAAAGAGCAACUACUCUUUCUUAAAUCAAUCUACAAUUCACAGAUAGGAAGAGGUCAAUGACCUAGGAGUAACAAUCAACUCAAGAUUCAUUUUCAUUAUGUUAUUCAUGAACACCCGGAGCACUACACUAUAAUGCACAAAUGGAUACUGACAUGGAUCCUGCCAACUUUGCUCUACAGAUCAUGCUUUCACAUUAUCUGUCUAGUGGGUACUAUAUCUUUAGCUUGCAAUGACAUGACUCCAGAGCAAAUGGCUACAAAUGUGAACUGUUCCAGCCCUGAGCGACACACAAGAAGUUAUGAUUACAUGGAAGGAGGGGAUAUAAGAGUGAGAAGACUCUUCUGUCGAACACAGUGGUACCUGAGGAUCGAUAAAAGAGGCAAAGUAAAAGGGACCCAAGAGAUGAAGAAUAAUUACAAUAUCAUGGAAAUCAGGACAGUGGCAGUUGGAAUUGUGGCAAUCAAAGGGGUGGAAAGUGAAUUCUAUCUUGCAAUGAACAAGGAAGGAAAACUCUAUGCAAAGAAAGAAUGCAAUGAAGAUUGUAACUUCAAAGAACUAAUUCUGGAAAACCAUUACAACACAUAUGCAUCAGCUAAAUGGACACACAACGGAGGGGAAAUGUUUGUUGCCUUAAAUCAAAAGGGGAUUCCUGUAAGAGGAAAAAAAACGAAGAAAGAACAAAAAACAGCCCACUUUCUUCCUAUGGCAAUAACUUAAUUGCAUAUGGUAUAUAAAGAACCAGUUCCAGCAGGGAGAUUUCUUUAAGUGGACUGUUUUCUUUCUUCUCAAAAUUUUCUUUCCUUUUAUUUUUUAGUAAUCAAGAAAGGCUGGAAAACUACUGAAAAACUGAUCAAGCUGGACUUGUGCAUUUAUGUUUGUUUUAAGACACUGCAUUAAAGAAAGAUUUGAAAAGUAUACACAAAAAUCAGAUUUAGUAACUAAAGGUUGUAAAAAAUUGUAAAACUGGUUGUACAAUCAUGAUGUUAGUAACAGUAAUUUUUUUCUUAAAUUAAUUUACCCUUAAGAGUAUGUUAGAUUUGAUUAUCUGAUAAUGAUUAUUUAAAUAUUCCUAUCUGCUUAUAAAAUGGCUGCUAUAAUAAUAAUAAUACAGAUGUUGUUAUAUAAGGUAUAUCAGACCUACAGGCUUCUGGCAGGAUUUGUCAGAUAAUCAAGCCACACUAACUAUGGAAAAUGAGCAGCAUUUUAAAUGCUUUCUAGUGAAAAAUUAUAAUCUACUUAAACUCUAAUCAGAAAAAAAAUUCUCAAAAAAACUAUUAUGAAAGUCAAUAAAAUAGAUAAUUUAACAAAAGUACAGGAUUAGAACAUGCUUAUACCUAUAAAUAAGAACAAAAUUUCUAAUGCUGCUCAAGUGGAAAGGGUAUUGCUAAAAGGAUGUUUCCAAAAAUCUUGUAUAUAAGAUAGCAACAGUGAUUGAUGAUAAUACUGUACUUCAUCUUACUUGCCACAAAAUAACAUUUUAUAAAUCCUCAAAGUAAAAUUGAGAAAUCUUUAAGUUUUUUUCAAGUAACAUAAUCUAUCUUUGUAUAAUUCAUAUUUGGGAAUAUGGCUUUUAAUAAUGUUCUUCCCACAAAUAAUCAUGCUUUUUUCCUAUGGUUACAGCAUUAAACUCUAUUUUAAGUUGUUUUUGAACUUUAUUGUUUUGUUAUUUAAGUUUAUGUUAUUUAUAAAAAAAAAACCUUAAUAAGCUGUAUCUGUUUCAUAUGCUUUUAAUUUUAAAGGAAUAACAAAACUGUCUGGCUCAACGGCAAGUUUCCCUCCCUUUUCUGACUGACACUAAGUCUAGCACACAGCACUUGGGCCAGCAAAUCCUGGAAGGCAGACAAAAAUAAGAGCCUGAAGCAAUGCUUACAAUAGAUGUCUCACACAGAACAAUACAAAUAUGUAAAAAAUCUUUCACCACAUAUUCUUGCCAAUUAAUUGGAUCAUAUAAGUAAAAUCAUUACAAAUAUAAGUAUUUACAGGAUUUUAAAGUUAGAAUAUAUUUGAAUGCAUGGGUAGAAAAUAUCAUAUUUUAAAACUAUGUAUAUUUAAAUUUAGUAAUUUUCUAAUCUCUAGAAAUCUCUGCUGUUCAAAAGGUGGCAGCACUGAAAGUUGUUUUCCUGUUAGAUGGCAAGAGCACAAUGCCCAAAAUAGAAGAUGCAGUUAAGAAUAAGGGGCCCUGAAUGUCAUGAAGGCUUGAGGUCAGCCUACAGAUAACAGGAUUAUUACAAGGAUGAAUUUCCACUUCAAAAGUCUUUCAUUGGCAGAUCUUGGUAGCACUUUAUAUGUUCACCAAUGGGAGGUCAAUAUUUAUCUAAUUUAAAAGGUAUGCUAACCACUGUGGUUUUAAUUUCAAAAUAUUUGUCAUUCAAGUCCCUUUACAUAAAUAGUAUUUGGUAAUACAUUUAUAGAUGAGAGUUAUAUGAAAAGGCUAGGUCAACAAAAACAAUAGAUUCAUUUAAUUUUCCUGUGGUUGACCUAUACGACCAGGAUGUAGAAAACUAGAAAGAACUGCCCUUCCUCAGAUAUACUCUUGGGAGAGAGCAUGAAUGGUAUUCUGAACUAUCACCUGAUUCAAGGACUUUGCUAGCUAGGUUUUGAGGUCAGGCUUCAGUAACUGUAGUCUUGUGAGCAUAUUGAGGGCAGAGGAGGACUUAGUUUUUCAUAUGUGUUUCCUUAGUGCCUAGCAGACUAUCUGUUCAUAAUCAGUUUUCAGUGUGAAUUCACUGAAUGUUUAUAGACAAAAGAAAAUACACACUAAAACUAAUCUUCAUUUUAAAAGGGUAAAACAUGACUAUACAGAAAUUUAAAUAGAAAUAGUGUAUAUACAUAUAAAAUACAAGCUAUGUUAGGACCAAAUGCUCUUUGUCUAUGGAGUUAUACUUCCAUCAAAUUACAUAGCAAUGCUGAAUUAGGCAAAACCAACAUUUAGUGGUAAAUCCAUUCCUGGUAGUAUAAGUCACCUAAAAAAGACUUCUAGAAAUAUGUACUUUAAUUAUUUGUUUUUCUCCUAUUUUUAAAUUUAUUAUGCAAAUUUUAGAAAAUAAAAUUUGCUCUAGUUACACACCUUUAGAAUUCUAGAAUAUUAAAACUGUAAGGGGCCUCCAUCCCUCUUACUCAUUUGUAGUCUAGGAAAUUGAGAUUUUGAUACACCUAAGGUCACGCAGCUGGGUAGAUAUACAGCUGUCACAAGAGUCUAGAUCAGUUAGCACAUGCUUUCUACUCUUCGAUUAUUAGUAUUAUUAGCUAAUGGUCUUUGGCAUGUUUUUGUUUUUUAUUUCUGUUGAGAUAUAGCCUUUACAUUUGUACACAAAUGUGACUAUGUCUUGGCAAUGCACUUCAUACACAAUGACUAAUCUAUACUGUGAUGAUUUGACUCAAAAGGAGAAAAGAAAUUAUGUAGUUUUCAAUUCUGAUUCCUAUUCACCUUUUGUUUAUGAAUGGAAAGCUUUGUGCAAAAUAUACAUAUAAGCAGAGUAAGCCUUUUAAAAAUGUUCUUUGAAAGAUAAAAUUAAAUACAUGAGUUUCUAACAAUUAGAAAAGAAAAAAUUAAAACAUGAAAUGAUAACAAAAGUAAACAAAAGAUACUUUCAAAGCAGUGAACAAAACAUUUUGACAUAAGCCAUAAUAUAAAUUAUAAUAUAAAAAAUAAAAACCAUAGUAUAAAUUGUCAGCCUUUGAGUUGGCUACAAAUUCAAUUUAAUGACAGAAGAGAAGGGAUGCUGGAGGUAAAUUCUUAGGGUUUCUAUCUCAUAGAGUUUGCUCUUCUGGUUCUCUAGACUGCCAAAGAACAUAAAGAUGUGCGAGGGGACCUAGCUGUAGUAAAAGCAAUCCUAUAACAAGAAAAACUCUAAAACAGUGCCCCUUACGAUUUUCUACUGAAAUUUCUCUAAUAGUAGAGGUGUAAAAUAAGAAGUUAGAGAAUAAUGCAAAGGGGGCCCACCACAGACGGAACAUUUCUUUUCUCUUAAGACUCAUGUGAUUUUUGCAUCUUACUCCAUAAUAUAUUUGUGGUUGCGUUAAUAUGACAAUGUCUGCAAUUAAACACCAGUAAGCAAAAUUGAUACAUCAGAAUGACUUGCAGGGCUUAUCAUGCAGUUUGGUUUACAUCCCUACUCCACUGCCAUUUACUUGAGCGUGAAUGAGACACAAAAGAUUAUUUGCCUCCCAUAAUCCAACUUUACACAUAAAUAACACAAGGCUAAAGAAAACCAGAACUCAAAUUCACCACGCAUAGGAGUGAUAACAAAAAUAUUUAACAGUCAGUAUGGGUGAUUACUGGCCAAUCAGAAUACAUCACUGAUACAUCGAAAUGGAUGCAGGCCACUAUGACUAACUUGUGGGUAUCAUUUCUAUGAUCACCCUAAAACAGAGUUGGGAAAAUAUCUAUUAACUGGUCUCUCUGGUUUGAAUUCUCAAUAUGUAUCUUAAUAUGAAAUAGCUCAUUAAAACUUCAUGUGUAACUAUUUCAGCAUUGUUGUCAGCUACUCUUUAUUCCACUUCUGUACAGUAUUUAUUCAACCAAGCUGCUGCUUUCAAUGAAGGUCACUUGUUCCUUCAGGGACACAUAUACUCCCACCUAUCCUUUAAUUUUGAAUGGUUUGUCAGGAAAAUUUACUUUCUCUUGAGUUGAAAAACUUGACAGGAAGCAAGAAAUAAUACAGUCCUAGCCUCUUUCCAAUAACAUCUGAUUUCUCCAUUCUCAAACUACACUUCUCAAGGAACCAGAUAUUUACUCUCAUCUGGGAAGAUGCCUCUUAUGUUUUCCUUUUACUUCCUGGUUAUCAUGUGGUUGCAUUUUCCAAGUUCUUAUCAUUGAAUUUAUGAGAGCCUAUCAAAAUUUAUUUUCUUUCAUUUAUAUUCUAAUAAUUGAAAUGUGAGAUGAAAAUAACAUUUCACUUAUGAAAAACCCUUCUCUUGAUGAAUCCUUCCAUGUGUUAGUUAUCUAUUGCUGUGUAACAAAUUAAAACUUAAUGGCUUGAAACAAA